AGUUGUGACCAUUGCUUGAAACCCAUUCCUAUGGCACGCACGAAGCAAACAGCUCGUAAGUCCACUGGCGGCAAAGCCCCGCGCAAGCAGCUGGCCACUAAGGCGGCUCGCAAAAGCGCGCCAGCCACCGGUGGCGUGAAGAAGCCCCACCGCUACAGGCCUGGUACUGUCGCCCUCCGUGAAAUCCGCCGCUAUCAGAAAUCGACUGAGCUACUGAUUCGCAAGCUACCAUUCCAGCGUCUGGUACGUGAGAUCGCGCAGGACUUCAAGACCGACCUGCGCUUCCAGAGCUCGGCUGUGAUGGCGCUGCAGGAGGCCUGCGAGGCUUACCUGGUGGGGCUCUUUGAGGACACCAACCUGUGUGCUAUCCACGCCAAGCGAGUGACUAUCAUGCCCAAGGACAUCCAGCUCGCUCGCCGCAUUCGCGGAGAGAGGGCAUAAGUUGUACUGAGGGUGUGCGCCAACUUAAACCAAAGGCUCUUUUCAGAGCCACC